GUCAGAAGGUGGAAAUCUCUCUGUGAGAAGCUGCCAUCUCCCCGCCACCCGCUCGUCCCCUUCUCUUUCUGCCACCCUCCUUUCCUUCCUCCCUCGCUCCACUCCACUCCCUCCCUCUUUUCUCAGUACCCUCCUCUUUACUCUCCGAGUUAACUGAGAGCCGACCUGACAUCUCCAACAUUUUCACCCUCUUCCCCCACCCCCAUCACCGAGAAUGGAGUCAGGGUUUCCGGAGAGACCGAACUCUGCUCUCAGCACCUUUCCCAGCCGCUGUUGCUAAACUGACCUCGGAGGACGAGAGGGGAAGGAGGUGCGACGCCCCUUACAUCAGUACAAAACUACCACACCAACCACCUCCACUUCAAAGCCGGAUUUUGCAUCCUGGGGGCGGGACAGACCUCGUCCCGGGCUGAAUUCUCUCUCCACUCUUCGAGAUUGGCACACCCAGAGAUGCCCUGCCCAGUGAAGAGGAAUCUAGAGAGGCAGCCUGGCCACAGCCGCUUCGCUGCCCUGCGAAUGAAGAAGAUGAGCAACAUUUAUGAGUCCGCUGCCAACACACUGGGAAUCUUUAACAGCCCCUGCCUGACCAAAGUUGAGCUGCGUGUGGCGUGCAAAGGCAUUUCUGACAGAGAUGCCCUUUCCAAACCAGACCCCUGUGUCAUCCUCAAGAUGCAGUCUCAUGGGCAGUGGUUUGAGGUUGACAGGACUGAGGUGAUUCGCACCUGCAUAAACCCAGUGUACUCAAAACUGUUUACUGUGGACUUUUACUUUGAGGAGGUGCAGCGCCUGCGGUUUGAAGUCCAUGACAUCAGCAGCAACCACAAUGGGCUGAAGGAGGCCGACUUCCUUGGUGGCAUGGAGUGCACACUUGGCCAGAUUGUUUCCCAGAGAAAGCUGUCCAAAUCCUUGCUGAAGCAUGGGAACACAGCAGGGAAAUCUUCCAUCACGGUGAUUGCUGAAGAAUUAUCUGGCAAUGACGACUAUGUUGAGCUUGCAUUCAAUGCACGGAAAUUGGAUGACAAGGAUUUCUUCAGUAAAUCUGACCCAUUUCUGGAAAUUUUUCGUAUGAAUGAUGAUGCAACUCAGCAGCUGGUGCACCGAACUGAGGUUGUGAUGAAUAACUUAAGCCCAGCCUGGAAAUCAUUCAAAGUAUCUGUAAAUUCUCUAUGCAGCGGAGACCCAGACCGCCGGCUAAAGUGCAUAGUAUGGGACUGGGACUCCAAUGGCAAGCAUGACUUCAUUGGAGAAUUCACCUCGACAUUCAAGGAGAUGAGAGGAGCAAUGGAAGGGAAACAGGUGCAGUGGGAGUGCAUCAAUCCCAAGUACAAAGCCAAGAAGAAGAAUUACAAGAACUCAGGCACUGUGAUUCUGAAUCUGUGCAAGAUUCACAAGAUGCAUUCUUUCUUGGACUACAUCAUGGGUGGCUGCCAAAUCCAGUUUACAGUAGCUAUAGAUUUCACUGCCUCAAACGGGGACCCCAGGAACAGCUGUUCCUUGCACUACAUCCACCCUUACCAACCCAAUGAGUAUCUGAAAGCUUUGGUAGCUGUGGGGGAGAUUUGCCAAGACUAUGACAGUGACAAAAUGUUCCCUGCCUUUGGGUUUGGCGCCAGGAUACCUCCAGAGUACACGGUCUCUCAUGACUUUGCAAUCAACUUUAAUGAAGACAACCCAGAAUGUGCAGGAAUUCAAGGAGUUGUGGAAGCCUAUCAGAGCUGUCUUCCUAAGCUCCAACUCUACGGUCCCACCAACAUUGCCCCCAUCAUCCAGAAGGUUGCCAAGUCAGCGUCAGAGGAAACUAACACCAAGGAGGCAUCGCAAUACUUCAUCCUGCUGAUCCUGACAGAUGGUGUUAUCACAGACAUGGCCGACACCCGGGAGGCCAUUGUCCAUGCCUCCCACCUCCCCAUGUCAGUCAUCAUCGUGGGAGUAGGGAACGCUGACUUCAGUGACAUGCAGAUGCUGGACGGUGAUGAUGGGAUUCUGAGGUCACCCAAGGGAGAGCCUGUUCUUCGAGACAUCGUCCAGUUCGUGCCCUUCAGGAACUUCAAACACGCAUCUCCAGCUGCCCUGGCAAAGAGCGUGCUGGCUGAAGUCCCAAACCAAGUUGUGGACUAUUACAAUGGCAAAGGAAUUAAACCAAAAUGUUCAUCAGAAAUGUAUGAAUCUUCCAGAACACUAGCACCAUGAACUCCCCACACAGUUUUACAGAGUUCUGAAAUACUAUUCCUGCUAAUAUUUCAUAUUUAAUACUUCUACUACUCCUGUACUUUAAAAAACCAACAACAUAUACACAUUUAAAAAUAGCACGUUUUGGUGAUUUUUAACUAUCUGACAAUUUUUUUUGCAUGUGUAGCCCUGAGGCCUGGAUCUGUUAAGCCCUUGUAUUGUUAACUUUUUACAAAGAAACACAGAUAACAAUAACUUACUAUUUACAUUACAGCAUGUCGCCUUGAAAUAAAAUGGUAUCUGUAUCCAUUUUUUAUACAGGUUUGUUGAAAUUUUGCUAAAUUUCUUAUCUUUACACUCUAAAGCAUUUUGAAACAUUUACUGAAUGUUGAUAGACGAAAUAUACUUGGUUUUAUCUGCUAUAGGAUGAGAGACUUUUUAAAAUGGCAGAUGCAUGGACUGUAUUUUGCAUGUUUAAAAUAAAAAAAGAAAAACCCACAUGGUUUUUGCAGUUGUUAUCUCUAAUUCCUCCCUGCUGAGAAUGGUCUCUCUACUAAAGAAGAGGUUUAUUUACUUCUUCUUUCUGAGGUGAGUCUUUUUGAGGUAAGUCUGGGUCAUCUAGCCCAGCACCUCUCAUACUUUAUACUGUGUACACAAAUCACCUGAGAGUCUUAUUAAAAUUCAGAUUGUGAUACAUAGGUCUGUGUGGGACCCAAGAUUCUGCAUCUUUAACUAGGUCCCAGGUGAUGCUAAUGCAGUCCCUGGACUAUACCAAGAGGAGUGAGGAUCUAGACUUUAGGGUGUCAUGAUGGAGACCAUCAAAAACAGCGUGGCUUCUAGUCUGCUUGAGAAUGGCACCUCUUCCUGACAGUAGCACAAAAGUCCUGCCUGUCUCCAGAGGUGACAGUAGAAAGUAAUGAGACUGACUCCAGAAGCUGCACACCUCAAAUCAGUCUCGCUGCUUUAUACUCACACCUCUUCCUUAGAUAAGACUAGAAAGUGCUCCUCCUGGCCAGUCCCUGCCCUCUUAAAAGUGGCAUCACACACCACUGCAUGGAUGGUGUCAAUCCCUAGAAGUGAUCUCAAAGCGUCUUCACUGGAACCACAACAAUAGAAACUUACACAUGGCAAAUGGCUAUGCAGUACAGCUCCCGAUAUCUGGUCCACUAAAUUGACCUUUGAGCUUAGUGUGGGAAUUUCUUGCCUCCUUUCUAUCACUUCUGAGAACAAAUUCUAUAAGCAGAAAUGCCUGGAAUUAUUGUCUGGGGUCGAGGUGUUUUGUUUCAAUAUAAGCUGGCCAGUCUGGAACCAAAAGGACGAAUGUUUAACUUGUAUAAUCUUCUUGCAGGGAAACAGGCAAGUGUUUUUGCAAGCAUAAAAGGCACAAAGUGGAGUUUAUUUUUGGUCAGAGAGAUGAAGAAGUAAAUCACAAGGCAAAAUUUGUUGUUUGUUUGAAGAGGGGAGCAGUAUUAACAAGCAAAUAAAAUGCCUUCUAUGAUUUCCACAGUUACAAUUAUAGAUCCUAAUCUUGCAAAUACAUGUCACCAAAUGCACAACAUUUUGGGAAUGAUGGUAAAAUUGUAUGACUGAAAAAAUCAUAAAUAUUUAAGCUAUAUUGUUUUAUUAAUAAAUUGGGUACUUACAGAA